AUGAUGUUGUGUUUGGAGAAAAGAGAGAAGAGAAUUGAAUAAGUACAUGACCCCUUGGAAGCUGUUUUCAGUUGAGGAUUUUGGUGAGUAGCCACUUGAAAUCAAGGGAAAUUCCAUGAAUAGCAGGAGCUGGGAAGAAAGGAAGAGGAGGAAGGAUCCCACCACUUUUUUCUUCCCAUCUAACACCGUGCUUAUGCAAAGCAUAGUCCAUAUGAGAUCUGCCUUAUAAAAACUUGCUGAAUAAAGCGAAUGGAAGUUAAAUUUUGGACUUUCUUCCAUAAUAGCUUCAAAUUAUGGUGACUUUGUUGCCUAUAGAGGGCCAGGAAAUACAUUUCUUUGAGAUCCUAGAAUCUGAGUGUGUGCUCUACACAGGAUGGAUAGAGCGAGCCUCUGGCAGUUCCAUUUAUCCAGAGGCAAAAGCACGCCUGCCACUGGAGGCGCUCUUGGGUUCCAACAAAGAACCUAUGUUGCCUAAGGAAACAGUGCUUUCUCUUAAAAGGUACAAUCUUGGCUCCUCUGCCAUGAAGCGGAAUGUUCCUGGACAUGUGCUUCAGAGACCUUCCUAUUUAACCAGGAUACAAGUUACAUUGUUAUGCAAUUCCUCUGCUGAGGCCCUGUAAAAGGAGUGAGUUAGGACAGAUGCAGCAAGAUAUUAGGACAGAUUUCGCCCAUUAUUCAGGCUGCACAACACAGAAGGAAACUUGAUUUCAAUAAGACCCAAUUCUUAACAGUCUUUUCUACCCACUUUUACCCAUAACUUUUCCAAAUUUGGUUCAAAUUGUGCAGAGAAACAAUAAAAUUUUUAAAAAGGAUAAACUGGCUAGUUAAAAGUAAAUGGCAUUUAAUUAAAACAAAUCUUGCAAAUUCAUGAAAAAA